UGCGCCCGGGCUCCCCUCCCCGCCGGCCCGGCACUUCCCAGCUCUGACGCGGGAGCUUCUUUCACACCAAUGGGGCUCGCGCGCGGAGGGGCCCUGCCCCUCCUCCGGGAAGGUGUGUCCCUGUUUCCUCACCUGAAACUUCCUAGGAGAACCCGAUCCCUCCCUCCCGUCGGGCGGCCAGGGGCGGGCCGCGGGUGGGGCGGCCGGGCCUGCGCUGGGGACGGCUCUGGGGACUGCGGCCGGCGCCGGGACCUGGAGGGGACGCUGGGGCCGAAGCAGCAUGUGACACCGACCAGGAGAUGAGGUGUUCUGCUGGAAGUGAGAAGAAAGGCAGGAAGGUCGAAAUCAAAAGACAGGAAGGUCAAAAGAAUUAAUGAGAAGAGUUCAUAUGGAUACUGAGGCCAAGGGGAGAGUAAGGUGAUGCAGAAAGCACCCUUCUGUGGUCUUCCUUCAAGGUGGUAAUGUGUCUAGUUCAACACUAAUCCAAUAAGGCUGUUAUCAUCCCACUUUACAACAGCUGCCUCUAGAAUUGGAAACAAAACUGUUAGUUACAAUGCUGUAGUAGACACUAUGGAAAACAGAAAGAUGAGUAAACUCCAAACCCUCUGUAAAGAAGAUGAAACCAUAGCACCUCACACAUUGGCUAUCAUAGCCUGGCCUAUUUUAACUGAUGUCCACAGCUUAAGAGGAAGACCCUCUCCUGACACUGCUUCUCUGGCCUAAUAGAUCUGAGGUGUGUCCCUUGCUGUGUCUGGGGGUUAUAUGAGGAUGAGUCACUCCUAGUGUCCGAAGAGUAGACAGGGAGAGACAGAAGAUGACAUAAUGGAGUCUAGAGAGAACUGACAACUGGGAGCUUCUGGGCACUCUCUGACAAUGGUCCUCUGCUAUAAUUUAAUUGUUCAUUAUGACCUGUUUCCCUCACAAGACCACAGUCUCCAUGACGACAAGAUCUUUAUCUCAUUCACUACUGAAUGCCCCACACUUAACAGGGUCGCUAGGAAAAUAUUUAUGAAAUAAAUACAUCAAUGACAAGUUUUUUAGAGGCUAUUGCUUAUUUUGUUGAGAACCUGUUGUCUCAAAGAAUGACCCUAAAUGGAACCAAAUAAAUGCAUCACUCUUCUUUUUUAUGGUCUCUUCCUCUGAUAGGUAAAAGCAGAGUUGUUAGAAACAUUUGUCUUUGAUUCCUCCUUAGGAUUCAGCCCUGAUGGAGGCUGAGGAGGCCCAGCGUGGAGCCUCUCCUCCCAUCUCUGCCAUAGAGGAAUUCAGCAUUAUCCCUGAGGCUCCCAUGAGGAGCAGCCAGGUCUCUGCCUUGGGGCUUGAAGCUCAAGAAGAUGAGGACCCAUCCUAUAAGUGGAGAGAGGAACACAGACUCUCAGCAACUCAGCAGAGUGAGUUAAGGGAUGUGUGUGACUAUGCGAUUGAGACGAUGCCCUCUUUUCCCAAGGAAGGUUCUGCAGAUGUGGAGCCCAAUCAGGAAAGCCUUGUGGCUGAGGCCUGUGACACUCCGGAACACUGGGAGGCAGUACCCCAGAGCCUAGCAGGCCGACAAGCAAGGACUCUAGCUCCCCCAGAGCUCUGGGCCUGCCCCAUUCAGAGUGAGCAUCUAGACAUGGCCCCAUUUUCCAGUGACCUGGGAAGCGAAGAAGAGGAGGUGGAAUUUUGGCCAGGACUUACUUCUUUGACAUUGGGAUCUGGACAGGCAGAAGAAGAAGAGGAAACCUCUUCAGAUAACUCUGGUCAGACCAGAUAUUAUUCUCCCUGCGAAGAGCAUCCUGCAGAGACCAACCAGAAUGAAGGCGCUGAAAGUGGGACUAUCAGGCAGGGGGAAGAGCUGCCAUCUGAGGAGCUGCAGGAAAGUCAAGGGCUCUUGCAUCCCCAGGAGGUCCAAGUUCUGGAGGAGCAGGGACAGCAGGAAGCAGGAUUUCGGGGGGAAGGAACUCUGAGGGAGGAUGUUUGUGCCGAUGGGCUAUUAGGGGAGGAACAGAUGAUAGAGCAGGUUAAUGAUGAAAAGGGAGAACAGAAGCAAAAACAGGAACAGGUACAAGAUGUGAUGCUUGGGAGACAAGGAGAAAGAAUGGGGCUCACUGGGGAGCCAGAGGGUCUGAAUGACGGUGAGUGGGAGCAGGAGGAUAUGGAGAGGAAGGCUCAGGGUCAGGGAGGUCCAGAACAGGGAGAAGAGAGGAAGAGGGAGCUGCAGGUGCCAGAAGAGAACAGGGCGGACUCUCAGGACGAAAAGAGUCAAACCUUUUUGGGAAAAUCAGAGGAAGUAACUGGAAAGCAAGAAGAUCAUGGUAUAAAGGAGAAAGGGGUGCCAGUCAGCGGGCAGGAGGCGAAAGAGCCAGAGAGUUGGGAUGGGGGCAGGCUGGGGGCAGUGGGAAGAGCGAGGAGCAGGGAAGAGGAGAAUGAGCAUCAUGGGCCUUCAAUGCCCGCUCUGAUAGCCCCUGAGGACUCUCCUCACUGUGACCUGUUUCCAGGUGCCUCAUAUCUCGUGACUCAGAUUCCCGGGACUCAGACAGAGUCCAGGGCUGAGGAACUGUCCCCCGCAGCUCUGUCUCCCUUGCUAGAGCCCAUCAGAUGUUCUCACCAGCCCAUUUCUCUACUGGGCUCCUUUUUGACUGAGGAGUCACCUGACAAGGAAAAACUUCUAUCAGUACUUUGAUAUGUCACAGUUUCAUGUUUAUCCAGUUCAAUGUAUUUUUAAAUUUUUCCUUGAGACUUCUUUGACUGAUAGAUUAUUGUGAAGUGUGUUUUUAAAUUUCCAAAUGUUUAGGGAUUUUCAUAUCUUUCUUAUGCUGAUUUCCAAUUGGAUUCCCUACAAUGAUUUCUGGUUUUCAUCUGCUCUGGAUGAUUACUAUCUCUUUUAAAUUUGUUGUGGCGAGUUUUAGGGCCUAGGACAGCUCUAUCUUGCCAUGUGUUUCAUCAGCACUCAAAAAAAAUAUGUGUAUUCUGCUGUUACUGUGUGGAAUAUUCUGUAAAUGCCAAAUAGAUUCUUUUGGUUAAUGGCAUUUUGAGUUGUUUUAUAUUCUUGUUGAUUUUCUUUUUUUUCCUCUUUUUAAAAACAUGAAAUGCUUCACAAAAUUUUGUGUAAUCUAUAUUCAAGAACCGUUUUAAUCUUGUUGGCAUCAUUCUGAUUUUAGAAAGUGCUGCCAAAGCCAACACUCCUUGCUGAUUUUCUGUCUAGUUCUAUCAAUUAUUGAAAAAGGCAUGAGGAAAUUUCUAACUAUAAUUGUGGAUUCAUCUAUAUCUCCUUUCAGUUUUCUUUUUUUAAAAAAAAUCAAUGAAAAUUUAUUAAAUUAAGCAUAAAGUUACUUUCACAUUUAUCUACAACCACAGUGAAUACAGUUCUUGGCAUGAAGACACCACAACCUUUAGAAUUUAAAGCCUCCUCACCUGCAAGAUUACAUAUAUAAAACUCCCACUAUUGUUUCUCUAAGAGUGGAUUAGUUCACCAAGUUAAAAGUUAUAUGAUCUAGAAUAUAAUAAAAUGGAAAUGAUUUACUCAUAA